AGAGUGUGCCGGCGCGCGGGGGAGUCUCGGCGCUGGGCGCGUCUCGGAGCCCAAGUCGCGGCCGCCGAGCGGAGCCAGCCCCUCCCCUACCCGGAGCAGCCCGCUGGGGCCGUCCCGAGCGGCGACACACUAGGAGUCCCGGCCGGCCAGCCAGGGCAGCCGCGGUCCCGGGACUCGGCCGUGAGUGCUGCGGGACGGAUGGUGGCGGCGGGGCGCGGGCCAGCGCGGGCGCCGUGAGCCGGAGCUGCGCGCGGGGCAUGCGGCUGCGGCCCCCGGCCCUCGGCCCCCGCGCUCCGGCCCCAGCCCCGGCCGCCGGCCCCCGCGGAGUGCAGCGACCGCGCCGCCGCUGAGGGAGGCGCCCCACCAUGCCGCGGGCCCCGGCGCCGCUGUACGCCUGCCUCCUGGGGCUCUGCGCGCUCCUGCCCCGGCUCGCAGGUCUCAACAUAUGCACUAGUGGAAGUGCCACCUCAUGUGAAGAAUGUCUGCUAAUCCACCCAAAAUGUGCCUGGUGCUCCAAAGAGGACUUCGGAAGCCCACGGUCCAUCACCUCUCGGUGUGAUCUGAGGGCAAACCUUGUCAAAAAUGGCUGUGGAGGUGAGAUAGAGAGCCCAGCCAGCAGCUUCCAUGUCCUGAGGAGCCUGCCCCUCAGCAGCAAGGGUUCGGGCUCUGCAGGCUGGGACGUCAUUCAGAUGACACCACAGGAGAUUGCCGUGAACCUCCGGCCCGGUGACAAGACCACCUUCCAGCUACAGGUUCGCCAGGUGGAGGACUAUCCUGUGGACCUGUACUACCUGAUGGACCUCUCCCUGUCCAUGAAGGAUGACUUGGACAAUAUCCGGAGCCUGGGCACCAAACUCGCGGAGGAGAUGAGGAAGCUCACCAGCAACUUCCGGUUGGGAUUUGGGUCUUUUGUUGAUAAGGACAUCUCUCCUUUCUCCUACACGGCACCGAGGUACCAGACCAAUCCGUGCAUUGGUUACAAGUUGUUUCCAAAUUGCGUCCCCUCCUUUGGGUUCCGCCAUCUGCUGCCUCUCACAGACAGAGUGGACAGCUUCAAUGAGGAAGUUCGGAAACAGAGGGUGUCCCGGAACCGAGAUGCCCCUGAGGGGGGCUUUGAUGCAGUACUCCAGGCAGCCGUCUGCAAGGAGAAGAUUGGCUGGCGAAAGGAUGCACUGCAUUUGCUGGUGUUCACAACAGAUGAUGUGCCCCACAUCGCAUUGGAUGGAAAAUUGGGAGGCCUGGUGCAGCCACACGAUGGCCAGUGCCACCUGAACGAGGCCAACGAGUACACUGCAUCCAACCAGAUGGACUAUCCAUCCCUUGCCUUGCUUGGAGAGAAAUUGGCAGAGAACAACAUCAACCUCAUCUUUGCAGUGACAAAAAACCAUUAUAUGCUGUACAAGAAUUUUACAGCCCUGAUACCUGGAACAACGGUGGAGAUUUUAGAUGGAGACUCCAAAAAUAUUAUUCAACUGAUUAUUAAUGCAUACAAUAGUAUCCGGUCUAAAGUGGAGUUGUCAGUCUGGGAUCAGCCUGAGGAUCUUAAUCUCUUCUUUACUGCUACCUGCCAAGAUGGGGUAUCCUAUCCUGGUCAGAGGAAGUGUGAGGGUCUGAAGAUUGGGGACACGGCAUCUUUUGAAGUAUCAUUGGAGGCCCGAAGCUGUCCCAGCAGACACACGGAGCAUGUGUUUGCCCUGCGGCCGGUGGGAUUCCGGGACAGCCUGGAGGUGGGGGUCACCUACAACUGCACGUGCGGCUGCAGCGUGGGGCUGGAACCCAACAGCGCCAGGUGCAACGGGAGCGGGACCUAUGUCUGCGGCCUGUGUGAGUGCAGCCCCGGCUACCUGGGCACCAGGUGCGAGUGCCAGGAUGGGGAGAACCAGAGCGUGUACCAGAACCUGUGCCGGGAGGCAGAGGGCAAGCCACUGUGCAGCGGGCGUGGGGACUGCAGCUGCAACCAGUGCUCCUGCUUCGAGAGCGAGUUUGGCAAGAUCUAUGGGCCUUUCUGUGAGUGCGACAACUUCUCCUGUGCCAGGAACAAGGGAGUCCUCUGCUCAGGCCAUGGCGAGUGUCACUGCGGGGAAUGCAAGUGCCAUGCAGGUUACAUCGGGGACAACUGUAACUGCUCGACAGACAUCAGCACAUGCCGGGGCAGAGAUGGCCAGAUCUGCAGCGAGCGUGGGCACUGUCUCUGUGGGCAGUGCCAAUGCACGGAGCCGGGGGCCUUUGGGGAGAUGUGUGAGAAGUGCCCCACCUGCCCGGAUGCAUGCAGCACCAAGAGAGAUUGCGUCGAGUGCCUGCUGCUCCACUCUGGGAAACCUGACAACCAGACCUGCCACAGCCUAUGCAGGGAUGAGGUGAUCACAUGGGUGGACACCAUCGUGAAAGAUGACCAGGAGGCUGUGCUAUGUUUCUACAAAACCGCCAAGGACUGCGUCAUGAUGUUCACCUAUGUGGAGCUCCCCAGUGGGAAGUCCAACCUGACCGUCCUCAGGGAGCCAGAGUGUGGAAACACCCCCAACGCCAUGACCAUCCUCCUGGCUGUGGUCGGUAGCAUCCUCCUUGUUGGGCUUGCACUCCUGGCUAUCUGGAAGCUGCUUGUCACCAUCCACGACCGGAGGGAGUUUGCAAAGUUUCAGAGCGAGCGAUCCAGGGCCCGCUAUGAAAUGGCUUCAAAUCCAUUAUACAGAAAGCCUAUCUCCACGCACACUGUGGACUUCACCUUCAACAAGUUCAACAAAUCCUACAAUGGCACUGUGGACUGAUGUUUCCUUCUCCGAGGGGCUGGAGCGGGGAUCUGAUGAAAAGGUCAGACUGAAACGCCUUGCACGGCUGCUCGGCUUGAUCACAGCUCCCUAGGUAGGCACCACAGAGAAGACCUUCUAGUGAGCCUGGGCCAGGAGCCCACAGUGCCUGUACAGGAAGGUGCCUGGCCAUGUCACCUGGCUGCUAGGCCAGAGCCAUGCCAGGCUGCGUCCCUCCGAGCUUGGGAUAAAGCAAGGGGACCUUGGCGCUCUCAGCUUUCCCUGCCACAUCCAGCUUGUUGUCCCAAUGAAAUACUGAGAUGCUGGGCUGUCUCUCCCUUCCAGGAAUGCUGGGCCCCCAGCCUGGCCAGACAAGAAGACUGUCAGGAAGGGUCGGAGUCUGUAAAACCAGCAUACAGUUUGGCUUUUUUCACAUUGAUCAUUUUUAUAUGAAAUAAAAAGAUCCUGCAUUUAUGGUGUAGUUCUGAGUCCUGAGACUUUUCUGCGUGAUGGCUAUGCCUUGCACACAGGUGUUGGUGAUGGGGCUGUUGAGAUGCCUGUUGAAGGUACAUCGUUUGCAAAUGUCAGUUUCCUCUCCUGUCCGUGUUUGUUUAGUACUUUUAUAAUGAAAAGAAACAAGAUUGUUUGGGAUUGGAAGUAAAGAUUAAAACCAAAAGAAUUUGUGUUUGUCUGAUACUCUCUGUGUGUUUCUUUCUUUCUGAGCGGACUUAAAAUGGUGCCCCCAGUGGGGAUUGAAGCGGCCGUGUACUUCCUCAGGGAUGGGACACAGGCUGGUCUGAUACUCCAGACUGCAGCUUGUCAAGUAAGCAUGAGGUGCUCGGGGCAGUGAGGGCUGUGCAAGGGGGAACACUGAGCAGAUACCUUUGGCCCCUUCCAGCUUUUACUGACAGAGAGUUCCAGGCUAGACACCAUAAAAACCACCCCUUGUUCUGAGGGGCUGAGGCUGGAAAUAGAUUGUACAGACAAGCAAGGGUUGAGUGGUGGUUCCCACACGAAGUCAUCUCUUAAUCAUCAUUAGCAAUAGCAGUUCCCUUCCAAGGCCUCCCCUCACUCCCGAAACACUUACGUCCCAUGCAGGCCCAAUGCAAAAAAACACAUUUGAGCUUUUUUCCCGCAGGGCCAUGAAGUCCCCUUAAGUUCCCAUAUCUAAGAUGGUUGACUGACCCUCUCCCCUUAUGUACAGAAGAGGAAACUGAUUCUCAGAGAGGGGAAGUGGCUUGCCCGAGUGUUUGUUAGGAGGUUACUGAAUGACAAACUGUUCCUAAGACCCCAUCUCAUGCUGGCCAGAGGGCCAGCCUCCUCAUUCCUGCUUGCUCUUAGAAAAUCUUUCACUGAUCAUUUUUUGUCACUGGAAUAACUUCAAGGUUAUUAUGCUUUCAUUCCAAAUGGAUCUGUCCUCAGCUCUGGACCCAAUUCCCCUUACUUCAUUUUGGCAAACACUAAGUCAAAUAGUGAAAUGCCUGUCACUACAUAGAACCUAUUACCUGGGGCAAAUACGAACAGAUUGAGUUUCCUUCAUCUUGUGUAAAUAUGAUGAAACAGAGACCUGGUAACUUGGUGACACUGUUAAACCCUUUUUGGGAUAAAGCCAAAUGUAAAUGAAAACAUUAAACAGAUAAAUUGUGGUGUUGAGACUUUUCUGAAUUGAGAAAAAUAAAUGUAAUUUUGGAAGAAA